AGUGUAACCAGCUGGGAGCCAGCCGGCAGGACGCUGUGAGUUGGCGUGCUAGUGGGAUGGCAGAUGAGGAAGAAGACCCCACGUUUGAGGAAGAAAAUGAAGAAAUUGGAGGAGGUGCAGAAGGUGGACAGGGUAAAAGAAAGAGACUUUUUUCUAAAGAAUUGCGAUGUAUGAUGUAUGGCUUUGGGGAUGACCAGAAUCCUUAUACUGAGUCAGUGGAUAUUCUUGAAGAUCUUGUCAUAGAGUUUAUCACUGAAAUGACUCACAAGGCAAUGUCAAUUGGAAGACAAGGUCGAGUACAAGUUGAAGAUAUCGUCUUCUUGAUUCGAAAGGACCCAAGGAAGUUUGCCAGGGUUAAAGACUUGCUUACUAUGAAUGAAGAAUUGAAACGAGCUAGAAAAGCAUUUGAUGAAGCAAAUUAUGGAUCUUGACACUUUUUGUAGUUUCCGAAAAUUACCAUCUGGGGAAACCAUAUAUAAUAAUUGUAUAUUUUCUAAAGUAAGAUUCUGAUAUCUAGCCAUGUAAAUGAAAGAUGGAGAAACACAAAGUUUUCAGCCUUUAUUUUUAUGCCUUUGAUUUUAGGGUGAUAUUGGUGCAUGUAAUUGCCUGCCUUUAUAUUACCAUACUUGAAUUACUUACUGGGUUUUAAUGACCACACAUAAGUCAAAGUACCUUGCAAACCAUGCCGUUGUUCUGACUUUUGACUAUUUAAAGGAUAAAGUAGUAUUUAAUGUGUUAGGUAUGUUUAUGCCCUUGUAAGCUAUACUGUAGCUUUUUUUUUUUUUUUUUUUUUUUUUGAGAUGGAGUCUCACUA